AGCCCCAGCUCUAAACCCGGCGGCUCAGCGGGCGCACCAUGGCACUGGAGUAGCGCGGGGAGCGCGCCCGGAGCCCCGCGGCCCGCUGCGCCCCGCCCGGGACCCCGCUGCGCCGCGCGCCCCCCCCGCGGCCCGCGGGGCCGCCCCUGCACCCCCACCCCCUCCCCCGCCUGCCGCCGCCGCCACCGCCACCGCCGCCGCCGCCUCCUCCCCGCGGCUCCGUCUGCAGCAGCCGCCGCCGCCGGGUUCCGGGACUGACAAGCAGGUGACAGAGGAGCCGGCGCGCGUGGCUGCAAGUGUCCGGGAGAGCGCGGCGCGGGCUGCAGCCGCCCCGGCCCGCCCGCACGACGCCGGGGCCCGGGGCCAGCGCGUCGCCGCUCCACGAUCGCCGGGGGCCGGCGCAACCCCUGCCCUGCGGGGGCCGCGCCUCCCCGGUUCCAGGGCCGCGGCGGCGGAGAGCGGGUGGACGGGCCGGCGGGCGAGCAGCCCGGCCGGCGGGGUCCGCAGCGCGCCCCGCGUCCCAUGGAUAUAGCAACAGGUCCCGAGUCGCUGGAGAGGUGCUUCCCUCGCGGGCAGACGGACUGCGCCAAGAUGUUGGACGGCAUCAAGAUGGAGGAGCACGCCCUGCGCCCCGGGCCCGCCACUCUGGGGGUGCUGCUGGGCUCCGACUGCCCGCAUCCCGCCGUCUGCGAGGGCUGCCAGCGGCCCAUCUCCGACCGCUUCCUGAUGCGAGUCAACGAGUCGUCCUGGCACGAGGAGUGUUUGCAGUGCGCGGCGUGUCAGCAAGCCCUCACCACCAGCUGCUACUUCCGGGAUCGGAAACUGUACUGCAAACAAGACUACCAACAGCUCUUCGCGGCCAAGUGCAGCGGCUGCAUGGAGAAGAUCGCCCCCACCGAGUUCGUGAUGCGGGCGCUGGAGUGCGUGUACCACCUGGGCUGCUUCUGCUGCUGCGUGUGUGAACGGCAGCUACGCAAGGGCGACGAAUUCGUGCUCAAGGAGGGCCAGCUGCUGUGCAAGGGUGACUACGAGAAGGAGAAGGACCUGCUCAGCUCCGUGAGCCCCGACGAGUCCGACUCCGUGAAGAGCGAGGAUGAAGAUGGGGACAUGAAGCCGGCCAAGGGGCAGGGCAGUCAGAGCAAGGGCAGCGGGGAUGACGGGAAGGACCCGCGGAGGCCCAAGCGACCCCGGACCAUCCUCACCACGCAGCAGCGAAGAGCCUUCAAGGCCUCCUUCGAGGUCUCGUCGAAGCCUUGCCGAAAGGUCCGAGAGACACUGGCAGCUGAGACGGGCCUCAGUGUGCGCGUGGUCCAGGUCUGGUUUCAGAACCAAAGAGCAAAGAUGAAGAAGCUGGCGCGGCGGCACCAGCAGCAGCAGGAGCAGCAGAACUCCCAGCGGCUGGGCCAGGGUGAGCCGGGGCCGGGGCAGGGCCUGGGCCAGGAGGUCCUGUCCAGCCGCAUGGAGGGCAUGAUGGCUUCCUACACGCCGCUGGCCCCACCACAGCAGCAGAUCGUGGCCAUGGAACAGAGCCCCUACGGCAGCAGCGACCCCUUCCAGCAGGGCCUCACGCCGCCCCAAAUGCCAGGGAACGACUCCAUCUUCCAUGACAUCGACAGCGAUACCUCCUUAACCAGCCUCAGCGACUGCUUCCUCGGCUCCUCAGACGUGGGCUCCCUGCAGGCCCGCGUGGGGAACCCCAUCGACCGGCUCUACUCCAUGCAGAGUUCCUACUUCGCCUCCUGAGAGCCAGCCAGGCGCACGGACGCUUGGGCAGGGGCCUGGGGGGGACUGCCAGCCUCUGCGGCCAGCCUGGCCACCCCCGCCCUGCUCUCCGCACAGACUACAGACAGCCAUACGGUGCCCUCCCCUCGGCCAGCUGGGCCUGACCACUGUGCCCGUUGGGUACAGCCAGACCGGUAGAUGGGCACAGCCUGGGCAGGGGCUGUGUCCUGCCCACAGAGACCUUGUCAUCCCCAGGGACCCAGAGCUCUCGGACGGCCACUCGCCUCCCAGCCCCACCUCGGCCUCCAUCGCCUCCUCCCCAUCUCUUUUUUGGGAAGCUUAAAUUCUCUCUAUUUUUUUAAAUGUCCUCUCUGUGUCCAUGGCCCUCCAUGCAAGCCCCAGGACAAUGGUGUCAUGAGGCGGUGACCUGAGAAGCGUGUGUACCUGUGCCCCAGCAAGGGCAGGGGUGGCCUCUGGGGGCAGGCCCACUGCCUGGAACCGCACACCCCUCAGCCUGAGUCUGGAGCAGCAGUGGAGAGGGGCCUGAGGGGAGGCACUGUCAGGAGGCGGGCUCGGAGCCUGAGCCUGGGCAGGCGCAAAGGGACAGAGAGGCACGUGCAGACACAUGCACACUUGCAGACAAACCCACGCAAACACACACACAGCUGUAUGGGGACACCAGAAGGGACAGGGAUGCUCAGCGGGUCUGUCCUGCCUUGUCAGAAAGAGAAAAGGAGGCCAGGCAGGGGACCCCCCAGUUCUUAAGAGCGAUUGGAAAGGGAGGAAGGGGAGAGGAAGAGGCGAACUUGAAGCAUCGGACCCAGUUGUAUCCCAGCCUGGGCCCAAAUGGGGGCAGCCUGGGCAGGGAGGGCAGCCCCAGGCCCCACCAACUCUAGAGGCAGAUGGAGCCCCCAGAACCAGGUAGCAUCAGACCAGACAACAGAGCCUCCAGGGGUCAGGGACUUCAGAAGCACCUGCUGGGCACCCCAUCUGCAAUGUGGUCCUCUCCCCAGCCACCUCUGCCUCCCCUCACAUACCUCCAGUGACAAGGAGCUCACUAGGUCAGCGAGCCCACAGCAGCUGUGCUGUCCUGCAUCCCAGAGCCAGGCUUCCCCAGCUCUCCCUCUUAACACUGUCCCCCAGCAGGCCUCCGGCUGUCCCUCUAAAGGUGUGGGGCAGGUAUCACUUCACCUUCCCACUGAUGUCAGCCGGCCAGAAGUGAGCAGGCACAUCACCUCUCCUGCUGUGGCACCCUUCCUCUGUUAAUUUGGCCCAAAAGACAAUGAUUUGGCCACAUGACCUUAGAGAUUCACCCUGCCCUGCUGUAGCUAAAUCCCUGGGCCCCACACGCAAGUGACAGCUAAGCCACAUCUGUUUUCUGUGUAUAUGCAGGAUGGGGGCACCUACUGUUUUGUUUUGUUUUGUUUUGUUUUGUUUUGUUUUGUUUUGUUUUGUUUUGUUUGAGACGGAGUUUCGCUCUUGUUGCCCAGGCUGGAGUGCAAUGGCGCGAUCUCGGCUCACCACAACCUCCGCCUCCCAGGUUCAAGUGAUUCUGAUGCCUCAGCCUCCCUAGUAGCUGAGAUUACAGGCAUGCGCCACCACACCCAGCUAAUUUUGUAUUUUUAGUAGCAACGGGGUUUCUCCAUGUUGGUCAGGCUGGUCUCCAACCCCCGACCUCAGGUGAUCCGCCUGCCUCGGCCUCCCAAAGUGCUGGGAUUACAGGCGUGAGCCACCGCACCCAGUCUGCACUUACUGUUUAGACUGAAUGAGGGACCGUGACCUCUUUCCUUUUCCAUUCCUUCUUACUCGAUUCAUUCCAGCCUGUGGAAUUUCUCUGCACCCUGAUUCAGUGACCACUGCUCUCCUCUCUCCCAGCACAUCUGCCCAGUGAGGAGUUGGCCCUGGGUCUCACCUGAGGUGUGUGGACCGGGCUGGCCUCUCCCUGUUUGACAUUGGCCCAUUAAUGCAUCCUCUUUGGGGGACACAUUCCAAUUGCAUUUCCUGCCCCCUUCUCCCAGGGCAAUUGCAGAAGAUUGUGUCAGGCGCCCUGCUGGAAGUCAGGUGCACUAGAUCCAUCCCCAGCCCCAGUCUGCUCAACUCUAUCCCUGUCAGAGCAAGGAGGCUGGGCUGCUGGGGCCUGACUGGUGAGCCCACCCUGUCCCCUGGUGAUCACUGUGUCCCCUUGUUCAGGUGCUCACAACCCUACCUUUAACUCUGAGGUCAAGCCCUAGGCCACCACCCUAAAGUCUGCCUGGUCCAACCUUUGAGCAAGUAAGGAUAAUGAAUGUCCCUUUUCCACCUUUGGGGCCCUCUGCCUGGAUCUCUGGAAUCCUCUAAGUUCAACCUGUUCUGUGGUUUUGCUCCCGUUUGCUGGGAAAUUCAGUCCCCCCAGAAUGUCCUGGGCCAACCUCCUUGCCUGACAUGUGGCCUCGUGUCACCCAUUGGGCCCCAGCAGCCAGCUAGCCCUUCUGCAGCUCUUCUUACAAACAGAGCCUCUCCAAGGACCUCAGUUGAUGUUCUGGUCCUUCUGCCGCCUCAGCCCACCAGGGUCCGUGCCACCAUGGGUCUCUUGAGCAGCAGCUGCACUGGCUUCUGGAGAGACACCCCUCUUUCUCCUUUUGCACAUGCACCAUCUGAAUCGUGCCAGGGACAUCCUGGGCAGAUUCAGGGGCAGAUGCCCUAUCCCCCAGGAGACCUGGCCCUUCUCUCUCAGACCCAAUAAGUUGGAAGGGACGUCAGAAGCGGUCAUCUCAUCUGCCCCUUAUUUUAUAGUUGGAAACCCUGAGGCAAGAGAGGGAAAGAGGCCUGUCCAAGGUCCGGGUUAGUGACAGAGCUGAGCUGAGAACAGGGACGUUGUGCCCCACUGUCCCCUGUGGUUUGUGAAUGACCUCCAGGUCAGGGGGUCACAACUUGUUCUUAGUAAACUUGCCAGCUGUUGGGGUCACAUAUUCCCAUUCUGGGGCCUCACAAACCCCCGAAUCCAGCCGGGACCCCAUGCCAGGAGCUGGUCUAGGGACAGCAUGCUUGUGACCCACAGACUGUUAAAGCCAGAAGGGACCUCAGAGAGUCCCUUAUGCUGGAGGCGCCCUGUCAGCCGUGGCUAGGGGCCCCUUGCUCUAUGCUGUGCCUUGCUGCCCACAGGCUCCCAGACACCAGUGCCCACUCUGCCCAGCCCCGGACUGGGUGUGGCUCGCAGAUGAACAAGAUGCAGGGCCUGCCUUGAGGGGUGUCUCCUAGAAGGAAAGCCAGACUCUCCGGCCCAGCCAGAGAGUCCAGACAUGGCAGGGACCCGUUUCUCAGAUGAGGAGCCUGAGGCUCAGAGAAGGGAGGCGAUGUGUUCAGGGCCACCCAGCAGAAGCCUGUGGGGCUGGGCAACCUUCUCCCACUUUAUGGGAGGAGCUGCAGCCUUGGCUGGGAGCUGGGCGGGGAGUAGCCAGGACCACCCCUUGCCCGUGCCGUGACAUGGAACCUUCAUCACUAAGGGGGCUGGAGUGGGAAGAGGGAGAUAACUGUGUGGUCUCCAGAGCAAAAGAGAAUGAGAGGUGGGCAGGGGGAGUCUUGGCAAAAGACCAAGUUCCACUUCCCUGCUGGGGAAGUCAAGGCUCAGAAAGAGGAAAUAAUUGCCCCAGGUAACACAGGGCAGAGGAGGGACAAAAAGCUGGGCAUGGCCCCAGCCAGAGCCUCAUCUGCCUACUCCGUGAAGCCUCCCAGGUACUCUGCUAUCCUGGGAAACGCACAGGGAGGCCACACAGAGACACUGCUCACAAGAGUCAGACCAAGGUGCCAGCACAGCCUGGAAAGAGCUCAGAAAGGGGGUUGGUGCACGUGGCUGGGCAUCUUAGGAGGCUUCCUGAGGGUGGGUAAAGGUGGGAAGGCCCUGGCGCUGCAUCAGAUGAGCAGGGCCUGGCAGGGACAAGCCUCUUCUCCUUUGGGAAGCCCUGCAGCCUCCUAGCAAGAGGCUGAUUCCCCACUCUGCCCCCAUCUGAAUGUCCUUUUCAUGUUGCACGCAGGGAACCUCAGGAAGGAGGAUUGCCUGAUGCCUGCCUGGCUCCAUCCUUGAGCUCUGGGCACCACCUAGGGUGAGGGAGAGCCUGCAGCUCUGGGGCUAAGUCUGCCCUGGGGGGAAAGGGCUCCACGCUCACACGCACGCGCUCGCACACACACACUCACACCUGGACGCACACGGAGGCUUGCGGACCCAUACUCACAGGCACAUGUGGCCUGGGGACUGGGGGAGCAGGAAAGACCCCUCCAACAUUUGGCCCUUGGAAGGCACCAUUGCCAAUGAGCCUCUUUGCUGGUUCCCCCGACCCCACCUGGGGGUCCCAUGGGAGCCCAGCCCAGCCAGGUGUGGGGAUGGGCCACCGGCCAUUCCUGUUUUCCUUGUACAGACAGAUUCUCACUACCCACCCGCCAUCCCCAGACACAUUUUAUUUAAUAACUUGUCAUUGUUAAAUUAUUUAUUAGCGUUUACCACACCACCACCCCCACCCUGCCCUCCACUCUCACCUUCCACCUCUUCCCACAACAGCAGAAAAUGGAAACAACAACAAAAAAAGAUGAGACAUCAGUAUAUUUGUAAAUAAACCGACCUGUACACUC